GUUGGUCCGCGCGUUGCUGCGUUGUGAGGGGUGUCAGCUCAGUGCAUCCCAGGCAGCUCUUAGUGUGGAGCAGUGAACUGUGUGUGGUUCCUUCUACUUGGGGAUCAUGCAGAGAGCUUCACGUCUGAAGAGAGAGCUGCACAUGUUAGCCACAGAGCCACCCCCAGGCAUCACAUGUUGGCAAGAUAAAGACCAAAUGGAUGACCUGCGAGCUCGUAGAAAUAUUAGGUGGAGCCAACACACCUUAUGAGAAAGGUGUUUUUAAGCUAGAAGUUAUCAUUCCUGAGAGGUACCCAUUUGAACCUCCUCAGAUCCGAUUUCUCACUCCAAUUUAUCAUCCAAACAUUGAUUCUGCUGGAAGGAUUUGUCUGGAUGUUCUCAAAUUGCCACCAAAAGGUGCUUGGAGACCAUCCCUCAACAUCGCAACUGUGUUGACCUCUAUUCAGCUGCUCAUGUCAGAACCCAACCCUGAUGACCCGCUCAUGGCUGACAUAUCCUCAGAAUUUAAAUAUAAUAAGCCAGCCUUCCUCAAGAAUGCCAGACAGUGGACAGAGAAGCAUGCAAGACAGAAACAAAAGGCUGAUGAGGAAGAGAUGCUUGAUAAUCUACCAGAGGCUGGUGACUCCAGAGUACACAACUCAACACAGAAAAGGAAGGCCAGUCAGCUAGUAGGCAUAGAAAAGAAAUUUCAUCCUGAUGUUUAGGGGACUUGUCCUGGUUCAUCUUAGUUAAUGUGUUCUUUGCCAAGGUGAUCUAAGUUGCCUACCUUGAAUUUUUUUUUAAAUAUAUUUGAUGACAUAAUUUUUGUGUAGUUUAUUUAUCUUGUACAUAUGUAUUUUGAAAUCUUUUAAACCUGAAAAAUAAAUAGUCAUUUAAUGUUGA